GGUGUUUGGUGGAGCCCGCGAUGGCCGAACCUGCGUCUGUCGCGGCUGAAUCUCUCGCGGGCAGCAGGGCGCGCGCUGCACGCACAGUACUAGGUCAGGUGGUGCUCCCGGGUGAGGAGCUGCUCCUGCCGGAACAGGAGGACGCGGAAGGCCCUGGGGGUGCAGUGGAGCGACCGUUGAGCCUGAAUGCUAGAGCGUGCUCGCGGGUGCGCGUUGUAUGCGGUCCGGGCCUUCGGCGCUGUGGGGACCGCCUGCUGGUCACCAAGUGCGGCCGCCUCCGUCACAAGGAGCCCGGCAGUGGCAGCGGCGGCGGUGUUUACUGGGUGGACUCUCAGCAGAAGCGGUAUGUUCCAGUAAAAGGAGACCAUGUGAUUGGCAUAGUGACAGCUAAAUCUGGAGAUAUAUUCAAAGUUGAUGUUGGAGGGAGUGAGCCAGCUUCUUUGUCUUACUUGUCAUUUGAAGGUGCAACUAAAAGAAACAGACCAAAUGUGCAGGUUGGAGAUCUCAUCUAUGGCCAGUUUGUGGUUGCUAAUAAAGACAUGGAACCAGAGAUGGUCUGUAUUGACAGCUGUGGACGAGCCAAUGGAAUGGGUGUCAUUGGACAGGAUGGUCUGCUUUUUAAAGUGACUCUGGGCUUAAUUAGAAAGCUAUUAGCUCCAGAUUGUGAAAUCAUACAGGAAGUGGGAAAACUCUAUCCACUGGAGAUAGUAUUUGGAAUGAAUGGAAGAAUAUGGGUUAAGGCAAAAACCAUCCAGCAGACUUUAAUUUUGGCAAACAUUUUAGAAGCUUGUGAACACAUGACGUCAGAUCAAAGAAAACAGAUCUUCUCCAGAUUGGCAGAAAGUUGAUAUAGGUGGACUUUUUUACAGGUCAGUUGAGGCAAAAAACUAUGGGUUUUUUCAGGUGAACCUCCCCCAUUUAAAUACUCAGAAGAUAAGGUGUGAAUGUAUGUAUUAUUAGAGUCCGAAAGUAUUUUUAUAAGUUACUGGUUUUCACCCACGCUUUUGUGGGAGAGAAAAUCAUUGCAAAAUCAUUUUUUUUGUUCGGUACAAUAAAGUUUACUAAAAAACAGUAUUAGGGUUUAUUUGGAGUUAACUCCCUUAGUAAUUGCUACAGCUUCCAUAAUUAACUGGAGGUCAGCAGUAAAAUAAUUUUGUGAUUAUAACAGUAAGCCAGGUUCACCAGAGGAAAUGUGGAAUACCUAAGUAUAAAGCAGCAAAGAAAUGUCACCUGUAGUCCCAUUAUUCAGCGGGUGAGUAUAUAACAACGAAAUACUUUUUCAUUUACCAAGUAUUGUGUUUUGCAUGGAUUAACUCCUUUAUUCUAACUGCAGAAGACACUUAUCCUCAUAAUUGAAACUGAGGCACAGAAUUUAACUUGGCCUACAUUCUCUAUAUUCAUCAAAUUGAAAUUAUAGUUAUUAUAGCUUAUAUGCCACUUUGUAAUAUACUUUUGUCUACUUCAAACAGCAUGAUACAUUUCACAACUUUAGUCACAUAUUUCAUGUUACAGGAUAUUUUUGAGUUUUAUCAUUAUAUAAAUAACACUAUGAGGAUUUCUGAAUCCAAAUCUGGCCAAGUCUUAUUUUGCUAAAAUCAUUUCCUAGGAGCUAAGCAUAGAAAACUCUUCUAUGCUAUUUAGUAUAUUAACCAAAACCUUUAGAGGUAAAGAGACUGCCAGGUGAUCCACAUCAGUGAUUCUUGGUUUCUAGACCUCUGAGAAUAUGUGAGAUACAGAUCCCCUGAAGCCUAUCCAUAGAAAGUCCUUUUUGGAUCAAAGAGAUUAUAGAACUCUAUUUGUUGAUAAAGACCAA